GUCGGGAAGAGAAAGGCGAUCAGGGUGGCAAGAAUGGAGAAGGAUUUGAACAGGUAAGAAAGAAUUGCAGAGGUUGGGUUGUGAUUUGAGAAUAAAAAGGCCUGGACAUAAGGAACUUCUCAUUUCUUCAGUUGUCAGCAAUAAUUGCUUAAGUCAGUUAAAAUUGUAAAGUUGAAUGUUUCAUUUGCGGGCCAUUUGGACCCAUUAUUUAAUUCGUAUUGUGGCCAGACUGAAUUGCGAAAAAGACACAGCACUUAGGGCAGAUAUCUUGCCUGAGGCCUAAGGUUUUUAGGGUUUUUUUUUAUGAGGCAGCCUAGAGGGCUGUCCUUUGGAGUGGAAGACUGGGAAUUUCCCACAACAGAGGGUAGGCUGAGAGAACAAGGAAGAGGAGAACAUCCUGGACAGCAAGAGGGGGACAAUAAAAGGAGCAAUUGUCACUGCUGCCAUUUUCGUUCCCAGAACAGGAUCUAAUGGCUUAGAGGCACCCCCCUAAGGCCAGAUGAUCAGCAAGUGCCUGACACACACCGGAACCUUCUUGGACCAACGUUGGAUUUUUGGACCAGAGAAAUCAAGAGAGGCCAUGUGGAUUUUCCCCUGUUAACAGGGCUCCCGGGAAAACUUACCAGUAGGCGAGAUCAGUGACCGAUGUGCAUGCACAGAGAGGCAACUGGAGGCUGAGGAGCUUCCUUUGUCCGGCUGCUGUGGCUUGCUCUCCGGGGUGGAGGGGUAGGUCCACAGGGGAUGCAGACCUGAGCCCCUCCCCGGUUUUGGCACCUGACUUAAGGUUCUUGUAUCGGUUCGAACCCGGAGAGCGCGCGUUCGAACCAACAGACAACACGAGGCGGUGUGGAGCAACAUGCUGUUUUAAUGAGUUCCUGGGUGCAGGCGGGCUGAGGCCUAAAAUGGCAUCAGCACCAAGUGAGGACAGGGCAAAGAUUUUAUAGUCUCCUGUAAACAGGAAGUGUCCUAGUCUGACGUAACUGCUACGUUGUACCUGGAUGGCCUCUUUCUUGAUCUUCACGGGUACGUGUCUUCCAGCCAGGGUAGGUGUCUUCCGGCCGGCUUUCUUCCUGCUUCUGCUAUUUUGCUGGCCCACACUGCUGGCGCAAGGCUUGCGCCUUGGUACUGGGCCUGAGAAGGGAGGAGUUAUUCAUCCCCUUAAGCUUUCAGGCCCCAGGGAGAAUCUUACACUACUGGGCUGCAUUUCCAGACAAUUAGGGCAUUCUAAGGCACAGGAUGAGGUAGGAGGUCCGCACAAGAUACAGGUCAUAAAGACCUUGCAGAUAAAACAGCUUGCAGUAAAUAAGCUGGCCCAAACCCACGAAAAUCAAGAUUUUGACCAGAGUGACCCUCUGGUCAUCCUCACUGCUACACUCCCACCAGCAUCAUGACAGUUUACAAACACCAUGGCAACGUCAGGAAGGUACCCUAUAUGGUCUAAAAAGGGGAGGCAUGAAGAAUCCACCCCUUGUUUAGCAUAUCAUCAAGAAAUAACCAUAAAAAUGGGCAACCCCUAUGGAGUAGCCAUUAUUUUAUUCCUUUACUUUCUUAAUAAACUUGCUUUCACUUUAUGGACUCGCCCUGAAUUCUUUCUUGUGCAGGAUCCAAGAACCCUCUCUUGGGAUCUAGAUCUGGACCCCUUUCCAGUAACUGUAUUACUGACCAUCAAAGGAAACCCCAUCUGAGCAAUGGGUUCCAGACCCCCAUCUCUAAUCGUGAGCCCCAUCCUGGAAGUCACUUGUAAUAAGGAAAGUUAUUCCAUAAGCUGGUCCUGCCACUACCCCUACAGGUUUCAAACACCCACCCUCCUUUCCAAAACCAGACCCAGGUUACUGUGGUCACCUACUGGUGACUUCAUUUGCAUCUGGUGGUCAGAUCUAGUCAGGGUGUAAUUCGGCUAAAUUAAUAGUGCUAAUAGUGCAAAUUCCUAGUGCGUUUUACAGGUGGGGAAUAGAGGGUGAGAAUUUGGGAUUUAAAACUGGCAUUUCAGAAAUGCUGUCACAUUAGAGCUUCAUUUCAGUCCCUUGGGGUGGCCACCAAGUAAACAGCUCAAUUUCCAUCCCUGCUGGAGGUACAGAAUGCAGCAUUCACACUUGCCAACAGAUAAUGUCUCCUGUCUUUGUCGGUGCUUAAUGGCUUUUAGUAGAGUUAAGGCUGAGAAGAAAGAGACUGACUUCCUCUUAUUGGGUAAAAUGGAAACACUGGGGAGACAAUUCCAUUUCAGACAGACCCUUUCCUUCUCAGAUUACUGAUCCACAACCCAGCCAACUCCCUUUCAGCUCAUUCAGGUAACAUGGAAGACAGAGGCCACCCGCUUAGGGGAGAGGAGGGUGGAAGAGCCCGUUGAGCUUUGUGUUUGGGAUUUGUCAGCAGAGAGGAGAUUUGCAUUUCUAAUAAGAGCCCCGUCUGGGUGUGCUUUAGCCCAGUGGCUGCACAUCUCUGUAGCUCUCCAAGUGCUCUCAGUUUGCAGAGCAAGGGAAGAAUCUUCUACAAAAACAAAUAGCUGUGGGAAGAGAGCAGAAAGCACAGCACAGUGGGGUGCCAGGGGCACUUCCUGGGUAUCAAGGAACGUUUAAAAAUGGUAUUACAUCAAGUCACCACAGACACCCUGGCGAAUAUUCCUCGUGUGCCCAUCCCUCACAUGCCCUUUGUCUAUGUAAGAGAAACUCAUUACAUGUUCUACUCUGAGAUUUGGAGAUUUAUUGUUAUUUCUCCAAAAAGAAGUAACGAGGCAUGUCAGUCCCAGCGUGUUUAUACAGCAGAAAACUGGGAAAAGAAAACAAGGUUCAACAAGAGGUGAAUAGUACGAUAAUUAAACAAUUAAAUAAAUAAAUGGUUAAAUACGUGGUAGAAACCUUUCGAUCAUAUAUGAAGUCUACAGUAUUUAGUAAUGUGAUUUUUUUUUUUUUUUUUUUUUGAGACAGAGUUCACUCUGUCACCCAGGCUGGAGUGCAGUGGCUCGAUCUCGGCUCACUGCAACUUCCAUCUCCCAGGUUCAAGCGAUUCAUUCCUGCCUCAGCCUCCCGAGUAGCUGGGACUACAAGCACGUGCCACUACACCCAGCUAAUUUUUGUAUUUUUAGUAGAGACGGGGUUUCACCUGUUGGCCAGGCUGGUCUGGAACUCCUGACCGCAUGAUCUGCCCGCCUUGCCCUCCCAGAGUGCUGGAAUUACAAGCGUGAGCCACCAUGCCUGGCCAAUGUGAUUUUUUUAAAGUGGUAAAUGUUAAAUGAAAAAUGCAGGAUUCAUACUGUAUAUAUAGUUUUUAUUUAAGAAAAACACAUAAUGCAUGAUGAAAUUACAGCAAAAUGUUAACAAAGUUGAGAUCUUUAGAGAUCAAAUCAGAAAUUAUUAUUUUUCUUUCUUUCAUUUCUACAUGUAUUCCAAAGGGUUUUUCGUGUAUGAUUAUAGAAGUUAUAUGUUGGAGCAGGGAACCCCACUAUACCCUCAUUACUUUUUUUUUCCCUUCCUUCUUUUUUUAUCUUGGGCACACACUAGAAUGUGGCAUUGCUCUCUGUGGGCCCAUCCGCACUCCAUUCAGCCAAGUAUUCUAUUGCUAACAGAGAACAGAGCAGGUUGCACAAGCAAUGGACAAAAUCUGAACAUUUCCAACUUCCCUCACCCCAUCAUUCACUCACCCAUGAGUUCAUCUAAACCCUUCUUCCACUUGUUUAUAUUUUUAGCUGGUACAGCCUCUCGGGCCCAGUGACUUCCAUGUGUUUUCCACCCUCGGUGUGAAGUGGCAGAGGCCUGCCCGGCUCGUAUCCUCAGAUGACCUCCUUUGGACUCCAAGGGGUCCUCCCUGUUUUUUACCUUUCCAGCAUUAAGGGAACAAAAUAAGAACCUCAAUGAUAUGUUUGCAAUUAGCAAAGCACACUUAUGGACAUAAUUUUGUAGAACUAUAGAACUUGGUAUUGGAAGAGGCCUUAGGAACAGUUUAGGCCAGUGUUUUCCUAAAAGUCCACAAUACAGGGAGUAUUUCCAGAAAUCACUGCAAGUUGUACAGUCCCCAGGAUAUGGUGGCACGGGGUGGCAUGGGAUCGUGGGGGGUUUGGUUUUGUUUUUGCUUCGGGCUGCAAUUGGAUAACAAUGGUUACCUCGUUUUGUUCAGAAACUCCAGCAGUUAUACAUAUGCCUGGUUAUUUUGUUAAUAGAUAAUUAAUGUAUGAGAGACAGAAUCUUUUAAACUUUGUGUUGUGGAGAAGGUGGACAUUGAUGGGACCCUCUAUUCUGAGCUAGAUCUGUGAGUGGAGAGGUCACUGCCUGAAGGUUGAGAAAUAUAUAUUCUGGCACUUCACUGCCUGAAGGGUGAGAAAAUGGGCUCUGAAGUGGCUCCCUGACCCCAGCAGAAGAGGCUGGUACAUGGGGCCACUGGACUAGAAUCCAGAUUGUCUGACUCUAAGUGCCAGGCUAGCUCCAGGGCACCUAUUCUACCUUUGUUUAAACCAACUUCCUGAGACGUGCUUCCUGCACUAGGAAUAAUUUAGUAGAUUUUGAAUUUGUGCAUGCUCCAAGUGUGGUCUUUCCAGACUGAGUCUUCUGUUUAGAAAAUGAUUAAUUAUUGUAAUUGCCUAAGUCCUUUACUCUUCCCACAGUUACUCUUUCCUAACUGUGGAAAUACAGACUUCCAAGUUUGGUAGAGUGUCGUGGGAAAGAAGGUAGGUUCUGGAAUCAGACACCCUAGGUUCAAAUCCUAGCUCUCCCACUCGCCAGUCCCUGAUCCCAGGUUUAACUUCUCUGUGCAUCAAUUUGCCCAACUGCAAAAUGGGAAUAAUGAUAGUAUCUACCUUAAAGGGCCGUUGUGAAGAUUAACCAUUGUGAUGAGUGCUUGUCAUUACAUUGCAUAGAAAAAGUGCUUUACGUUAAAAGUGGCUUACAUUACACUUGUCAUUACAUUGCACAGAAAAUUCAUUACAAGCACAGAAAGUACUUGUCCCAUGCCUCAUGCUCAGUGCAUACUCAAUAAAUAAGAGUAGUCACCAUCGUCACUGUCAUUGUCAUUACUGUUGGGUUUUCAUGGAAGGACCCUGGCCAGAACAGUGUCAGCUUAAACUUAUUUUGCUUUGCUGGACCUGUGGCCAUUACUUCCUUUUCUGUGUUGUUUGCUUUAUCCUUUAGAGAACAAUUAAACCUCUCCCCAUUGUCAGUACCCAUUUUAAAGAGCAAGACCCUGAAAUCCAGUGUGACUUGCUCAAGGUCACUCAGCUUGUCAGGGCAGAGUGGGAGGAAAAGCCCGAAUCUCCUGUUCACCUGCCAACAGCUCUUUGCACCAUGGUGCCAUGUUUCCUCUGCAUGCCUCCGUUCAUCCUCCACACCCGGAAAACACAGAGAAGCAGGAGAAUCAGCCAGAUACAUGAAAACUCUUGUUUCGAACACUGAGCAUUGACUGUUUACCUGGCCCUUGGUUCUUGUCUUUCUUUCGUUUUAGCAGCAGCAUUACGUACUGCUGCCAGGUGGAGCGUUGCUGGUUCCUGCUUCCCCUUCCUCCCUGCCUGUCUUCCCCUGACACUUCCCUGCAGGAAACCACUAGCCCUAAUGAGAACUCUCAAACGGUGGAGCAGAUGACAAAGGCGCUAGAGGCCUGGGGAUAGCGGGAAGUCAGCCGGUGACUUCCGCCUGGUUUAAAGCCCGUGUCUUUCCUGUAUUCAAUCCAGUGGCGCAUCAUAAGAAUUCCCUGAAGCAUUUAGCCACCUGAAAGGCCUUCUCUAAGGCCUAGAGAUCUCCCUAUCCACCACUUCCUGAGCACACCUUGCAGGUGCCAGACAUUUUGGGGUUGCAAAACCCACCUCCUGCCUCACAGUAGGGAGUCAGGAACAGACCGUGAACUACACAGAGUUCUUGUACAUACAGGGCACUUGGAGGGUCGGGGGUUGGGGGGCAAUCCAGGCAGAGGGGCAGCCUGAGCAGAGAGGCACAGUGUGAGUUCACAUUUAGCAGGCAGCUGAAUGCUUAAUUGUUCUCUGAUUGCUUUGAGGGUGUUUCAGCCCUCCAGCUAGAGAGAGUGGUUCUGGCUAGACAUGGUGAUGAAGCCUCCCUUUCCUCCCAAGCCCCUGCUUUUGUGGAGCUGAUUGACAGCUCGGAAAGCCUCUUCAUGUAUGUGAUUGUAUUUGAGCCGCUAAGCGUCUGUGUGAGAUCAGAUGUUAUCCCCCAUUUUACAGAUGAGGAAACUGAAGCCCUUAGAUGGUAACUCAGUGGCUUAGCUACCCAGUGACAACCUAAACUUGUACUGAGAUAUGAAGUCUCAGUAUGAGAUAUGAAGACUCCAAGUCCUCCCUAGCUCUCUCCCUUAUGGUCAGCUCUGGGGAAAUGUGCGCAGACAUAGUGCUUGACUGUAGAGCCCACUCUUAGAGACACGAAGAAGGAACAAACAAAUGAGCACGAGCUCCUGGGGCACAGUGAGAAGGGCACUGGCUUUGGAAGCGAGACCUAUAGCUCAAGUUCCAGCUCUUCCAGGCAUGAGUUGCAUGGACUUAGGACAGUCAUGUCUCUUUAUGUGGGACUCGGUUUCCCUAGUUGGAAAAUGAGAAGGUUGUAGGAAAUUCAUCUCAUAAAUCUAUAGGCCUGGGAUUGAGAACAUUGGUCUUCAGCACCUUCUUCUCUCAGGGCCCCCAGUCCUACCAGGCCUGCUUCCCCAGCCUACUUCCUACCACAUCCAUCCCUGAGUUCUUUCCAGGAGCAAAUUCUCCCAACAAACUGAACCGCUAGUUCAGUGGGAACAUCAGGGAGCUUGUUAAAAAGCUGACUCCUGGCUGGGCUUGGUGGCUCACGCCUGUAAUCCCAGCACUUUGGGAGGCCUAGGCGGGCAGAUCAGGAGGUCAGGAGAUCGAGACCAUCCUGGCUAACACAGUGAAACCCCAUCUCUACUAAAAACACAAAAAAAUAGCCAGGGGCAUGGUGGCAGGCACCUGUAGUCCCAGCUACUCGGGAGGCUGAGGCAGGAGAAUGGUGUGAACCCGGGAGGCGGAGCUGGCAAGUGAGCCGAGAUUGCACCACUGCACUCCAGCCUGGGUGACAGAGCGAGACUCCAUCUCAAAAAAAAAACAAGCUGUCUCCCGGGGUUCACCCCAGAACCUAAAGCCUCCAAAUCCCUGAGAGUCAAGGCCCAAGACUUUUCUCCCCUGAACACUCCCAGAAGUUCUGAUGAUCAGCCAGAUUUGGCAGUCUUUGCCUGCGCUUUGGGGUUCUCAAACUCAGUGGGCACUGAAUCACCUGGGAGCAUGUGAAAUGGCUGGGCCUCACCCCCAGAAUCUCUGAUUCAACAGGUUGGGGCAGGUGAGGCCCCCAAACCUGCAUUUCUAACAAAUUCCCAGGUGAUGCAGGCGUGACACUUGGAGAACCAUUGCCCCAGCUCAUUUUCUGAGAGCCCAACUAGCAAACCAUCAAAGGAACCUUUACUCGUGGGCCAUGGUUGCAGUGGAGCAUCCCUGACAGCAUGGUAACUUUUUAAACAGAGACCCUCGAAAUGAUUGAGAUAAUUACAGCAACAACUGCUAUUUACUCAGAUCUGUUACAUGCCAGACUCUGUGUUAGAUGUCCUAAAUCAGUAUUUCUCAUUAUUUUACGGAGCUUGGUGAUUCAAAAAUCAAGGAUCAAUGAGAUUAAGUCAUCAUCUAAGAGUAUACUUGUUACAAAUGUGAUCAGGACUUUCUAGAGCAAAACGUGGGCUAUUUUCUUUAGCUCACUAGGCCUCUCCUUGUCAUCCGAGCCAUGAGUGGCUCUAUUAUGGGAAUUUCAAACCAGGUUCAGACAGGGGUCAUUACCCAGGACUUUCUGGUUAGAGGAGCCUUUCAUUAGUUCCCCACAAAUUGUAUCCUACUGGUAGUGGCCUUUGGCCCCCACCGUGAGACAGCACUGCUGAGUGCUCACUUUUAAGGGACCCCUCGUGUAAACAGGGAUUGUUGCAUCUAUAGCAUUCUGAGCCAUUUGGGUGGAAACGGUGAACUGCUGCCGGAUCUGGGGAGACCCCACUUUAGUGGGUUUCUGCCUCGGUUCUGGGCUGGCUGAUGUUCUGUUUGGCUGUAAGGACCUUGGGAAAGAACUGUUGGCACCGGAUCGCAGAGAAUGUUCACCAGCUAGACGUGAAGGAGCUUAUGUCAUGACUGAAACACUUCCAGCUGGUGGGUCUUAGUCAGGGAGCUUCUUUCUCCCUAAUUUCUAAAGAUUUGUCUGGUGUAUAAUAGGAAGCUGAUAGAUUUGUAAAGAAGUAUAAAACACAGUAAUUAGAGAGGAAAUACAGGUGGCUGUGAGAGCUUUUUCUACACUUCGCUUUUUGUUCUCACCCUUCACACACACACACACACACACACACACACACAUCAUGCUUCUGAUUUUCUGCAGUUAAUUUUACAUCCGCAAGGACCUCAGGAAGUCCUUCAAGCCACCUAUGCCUUUCUUGGGGCAUCUCCUACCACGUCUGCCUGUGUUCCUCCCUAUGCAAGGACAAGGAAGCCAGGAGGCGGGAAGGAAAAAGGGAACUGCCCUGCAGGAAUUGAUCUCUUGGGGUGGCCAAAGGCCUCCACGCAGAGCUUGGAGAUGCUCAGAGGCUUCAGAGUGCUAAUUCUUUUGGUUUUGAAAGGGUAGACACAUAGGUCUUAGACAGGCUCCAUCCACACCCUCGAAGGCAGCUGGCAGCUCGGAAGAAUCAGCUGACAUUGCAAUUGGUGUUGAAACUUGACGACGCUAGUCCAGGGUCCACUUAUUAACCAUGCCACCUUCUCUGAGCUUCGCAUUGCGAAUCUGACCUGCUCUUCUCCCAAGAGAGAUUGUGAAGGCAAAAGAGAUCAUGGAUAUAAAAGUAUCCCUGCAGUCUGGGAUCUGGAAAGAACUCUGGGAAUCUAGAGGUUCUGGUUUACUAAUGAGAGAACUGGGGUCCGGAGAGAGGAGGUAACUUGCUGGAGGUCACAGAUGAGUGAAGUGACGAGGGAGGUAGAAGGAGGUCAGGGUGAGGGAAGACUUCUGGGAAUCUUUCUAGACAGAGCACCCCCAUCAGCUUCUAAAACAGAGCACUUUAUGACUACUAUUUCUCACUGAGUCUCUCUCUCUCUUUCUCUCUCUCUCUCUGUGUCUGUCUGUCUGUCUCACACACACACUUUUUGGUUUAAAUAGCAGAAAGGCAAUGACUGCUCUUUACAGGAGAGAAUCACACUCUUUUGCACUGACUGCAAGGAAACCUACUGGGCAUCAUUCAACUUUGCAAGUUAGAACAUAAGACAUGAAGUAGUAAAGGAAAACGCUGAAGAGAAUCUACUGCCCAAACUAGCUUGCAUGUGUGGGGCUUGGUGGCCUUACAGUUGCCUAAUACCCCCUGCCCAACCGUAUCAUCCCUAUGAUUUUCCACAAAUAAACACAUUCCUGGUCUCCCUGUGCCCAAACACACAUAGGGCAGAACCAAAGAACAUGGGCUACAAACACAGACAGACAAAGAGAAUUGGAAUUUUAUUUCUCACCAGCACUGUGACCUUGGGCAAAUUACUUAAUGUCUCUGAACUUCAGCUUCCUCAUCUGGACAAUAAUAAUACUUCCUAAUGUUGUCGUGAGGAUUAGCAAAGGUAAAGCCUAAAAAGUGCUGAAAUACAAGGGUUGGCACAAAGUAAGGUUAAUAAAUGUUAACUGCCGCUAUUGAAAAUGUUGGAGAUGAUAUUGAAGAUCACAUUAUUGUCAUUUUCAUAAGAAAAUUAACUUGUUUAUAAUUUUAAUGAGAUCUCACUAGGCUUCUAACAAUCUGACUGCAUAAUUAAAAUUCUGGUUUUCUACCCAGGAAAGAACUAAUAUUGUCCAGGUUUUAAGCACACUCUAGCUGGGCUGUUAUCUCUGGAAUACUGAGAUGUUGUCACGUGGUCUCCAAUAAUACCUUGUGUAUAUAAAUAUCCUUAUAUCUGAAAAGCAUAUAAAAUUACAAACAAUAAGAUGUACAGAUGAAAUGGAACUAGAAGGCAUGGAAACAAGAGUGUGAACACAAAAGCCCAAUUAUAAGUGGGGUAAAAGUUAAAGGUGCUGCACUUUGCAGUCUACAAAGUGCUUUUUAUGUCCCCACUCCUGGUGGCCCCACAGCCAGCCUAGAAGGUAGACAUUACUCUGCCCAUUUCACAGGUAAGGAAACCGAGUUUCAGCCAAGUGGCAGGACCAGCAUCCGGAGAACAGUGGUAGAUGCUGAGUCAGAAAAGACAGGAAAGAGCCACAACACAUAGGGCCUGGAGGACUUGGUAGAGCAAUUUGGAUUUUGUUUAGGGUUCAGUGGAAAGCCUUCAAAAGUUUAAGCGGGAGAGCGCUGCGACCUGAUCCACAUUUUUAGAUCACUGCCCAGAGUGGAGAAGGCAAAAGUGGAGACAGGGAGGCCACUUGUGAGGCUGCUUUGGAAGUUCCAGUAAGAGAUGAGGGCAGUGCCCGUGGAGGUAAAGUAGACAGAUUCAGAGAUACGUAGAGCAUCUAAAGACAGCCUUACUGAGGAUUGGAUGUAGAUGUUGGCAGAGAGGGGAGGAGGCAUGGUUUCCCUGUGGGUUGCUGGGUGGUUGAUUUAGGACAUCUUCAGGAGGAACCUGUUGGAGGUUGUGGGGAGGGGAGUUAGGGGAUCCUUGCAAACUUGUCAGGUUACAGUGACCUAGGCACGCACUUUUGCAAAGAGUCAGGUUCCCCAAACAUGCGUCCUUCUCUGGCGGAGAGCAGGUCUUAUUCUCUUGCUCCUGGGCAUUGACUAAAUGCUUUCUGUGAACUGAGUGAGCUAGAAUGCUGCCGCUGGCUCUGAGAAGCCCUGUAUUCCUUCUGCCACCAGGGAACCAGGGAGCAAGUAAUGACCCUUCUCAGAAUGUUGGGUCUGAUACAAGAAACAAACAAAAACCCCCGAUGUCCUACCUUCUAAUGUUUCAGACUUUGUGUAUUUUUUUUUUUUUUUUUUUGCCAGUCUCCAUGGGAUCUUUCCUCUGCUCAUGUUUGAAAGUGAUUCUCUUUUUUUUUUAAAUGUUGUUACUCAGGCCUUAAAUAACCUUUGUCCUAUGAUGGCUUCUGAAAGGAUGAAGCCUAAGUUAGUGCAAAAGUAACUGCAGCUUUUGCCAUUGAAAGUAAUGGCAAAACUGCAAUUACUUUUGCACCAACCUAUAGAAUUAUAAGAUCAACACCAACAAUAGGCAUUUGUAGAGUGUCAUUCCGUUAAAAGACCUCUCUUAUAUACAUUCCAUGAUUUUAGCCUCAUGAAAAUCUAAGGUAAGAUAAAUGGUGUGUUUAGCUCUAUUUGAGAGGCCAAGGAACGUAGCAGCCACGAGCAUGUGAACUACAAUAAUAGCAUUAAAACAUUAAAAGAGUUGAGCUGGAUAAGGUACUCAGAACAGGGCCUGCAAUAUGAAUGUUAGCUGAUGUUGUUGUUAUUGCGAUUAGCCUCCAGAUAGAGAAACUGAGGCAUGAUGAGGCUGUGAUGUCCCCACGCUCAGUAGUGGAAUCAAUUUCAAGUUGUGUUCCCAGAUGCCACCCUCAGAAGGAAUCUAUGUUCCAAAGGGACUUACAUUUGCACAGGAAGCCUCCUGCCAGGGCUGGGUCCUUGUGAAAUUCUUCCGUCCUCUGUGUGAGCUUCCCCACCUCUCCCCCAGCCAGAAAUCUCUGCACUUCUCCCGUCAAGUCUGCCUCCCCACUGAGGGGGGUUGAGCCCACUGUCCAGGACCACUCUACCCUGUCCUCCCCGCCCUGCCUCCUGCCCCAGGUGGCCUUCCCUCUGCCUGUCACCUUCCAGUCCUCCACCCAGUGACCUUCUCCAACAGGUUUCUCCAAUUGGGAGCACCCCGGGCCCUGAUGACAGGCACGUCAUGUCAUUGAGUCCAGGUCCCUCCUCAAGGGUGGGUCUUGGCAACAGAGGCCUUGCCUUGUACCUUGUCACUCUCCAUCCCUAUGUGCCAGGCCCAGUGCCAAGCCCAGAGCAGGUGCCCUGACACACUGUACAGCUGGCUUCUAAAAAACAACAAAGGUGGUCAUCACCAGAACCCACCUUCGCACAUGGGGGAUGUGCUCAUGAUGACUGUCCCCUUGGGGAACAUGCCCUUUAUUCCAAAGCUGGCGCCAGGGCCCAGGGCAUCCCAAGUUCCUGGAACGCCUGAGAGUACCUCACCACCAGCACCCAGCACCACACUCUCCUCUCUGGUGUUGACCAGUCUCCGCCCUCUGAAGGUGGCUGCAGUCACGCCUGAGGAACCAGGAGUGUGACUUCCCUUCAGAAACAGUUGAGGGGAGACAGGCAGCACAGGAGGCCCUUAGACAGUAAUGAACCGAGCUUUACUCUUCACAUCAUAGUACAACUCUGAAGAUGGCUCCAAACAUGGCCUUCCAAACUCAUCUUGGACAAGGGCCACAUCACUGAGGUAAAUAAAGGUAGAAAGUCCGCCGCAGGGAGCUCUUUCAAACAAUGGCUCUCCUUUGGUCGGCUCAGUUGAGUGAGCAUGUUUACAUUUUGCCCUCAAAAUAUAUUUUGAGGAAUGAAUGAGUGAGUAUAGCGGUGAAACCUCAUCAUCUCAUAGCCAAAGUGUGGGUUUGAGAGACAGCGAGUGUGUUGUUGCGUCUCUGUGUGUGUGUGCGCCUGAAAGAGAGAAGGGUCUCCGAACCAGAGACGGUCUCUUUUUGGAGGCAGCCCCCAGGCCACAACACCUCUUUUCAGUUGUCACUGAAGAAGGCGAAGAAGGCAGCCAGAGUCAGCCACAACGCUCAUUCCUUUGCUUCUUGCUCUCCCCCAUGGCCUGCAAAUUAGUUUCAGCCCAGUGGCUCCCUCCACUGACCUGAAUUUAAUUAUUUUAUUCUUUAUAAACGGAACACUUCCCCCAUCCCCUAUUCUCAGCCCCCCACCACUCCCCAGAUUAACUGACCACCCCUCAUUAAGGGUUCUGAGAAGUCGGUUUUGUGUGGGAAGACGUUUGGGUCCCAUUCACAGGCCUUGUUUGCAGGUCCCACUGUCCAUCUCUGUUCAAAUAAUGAAGAUUUGACCAGGCAGGGGGUCAGGGAGGAUGUUUUGCCUGGAUUCCCAUAUUUGCUUUUCAUCCAGUAAAAUAUUUUCCCGGGCAUUGGUGGGAGAGGGAAUGGACAAUCGCUGUUUCUUCAGAGAGCAAUUUCUAGUUGGCUGGCAGCGGUUCUGAGGCCGGCAGCGUGCCCUGCCCCUGGCAUUCCUCCGAUCUCGGUCCUCAUGGCCAGGGUGGGGCUGAAGCCAAGAGAUUUUCAGCAUGGGUAUCAUGGAAAGAGGAGGCUGUUUCGGAAUCCAGACUCUACGCAGUCCUGAGUGAUUGUGAUGAGUGCUGAGGUGCCACUGAAACCUGUUUACCGAGGCUGCUACCCACUAGGGUCUCUUCGCGGCUGCUUGCCUGUGAACUAAAACCGCCAGGUUGGAUAGAAUUCUCAGCAAAGCCCUGAAUCCACUGGUGGCUACCAAGAAACAUGGGAUGGCCAGGCAGGGACCUUUCUGGGUUUUUCAAGGUGGGAAGGUGAGAAUCGAUAGUGGGGUGGGCCUCUGGCCUCCCUGUUGGAGGCCCAAGAGAGCCUGGCACUGCCAUUCACCAGCUCUGUUCCUUGUGGCUCUGAGUCUCCGUUUCCCCAUUGGAGAUGUGAAGUUGAUGCUGCCUACCUGUGGGUGAGUGGCUCCGGAGCUAGACAUUCCCAGCUCUGCUACUCACUUGCUGUGUGGCUUUGGGCAAGUUGCUUACCUCUCUAUGCCUGGUCUUCCUCAUUGUAUUAGUUUCCUGGGGUUGCUGGGACAAAUUAGUACAAACUGGGUGGGUUAAAGCAAUAGAAAUUUAUUCUGUCACAGUUCUGGAGGCUGAGAGUCUGGAAUCAAGUGCAUGCAAAGCCCUAUUCCCUCUGAAGGCUCUAGGGAACAUCUUUUUUUUGCCUCUUCUGGCUUCGGGUGCUGCUGGCAUUCCUUGUGGCUGCAUUUCUCCCAUCUCUGCCUCUGUCUUCACGUCACCUUCUCCUGUUCUGUGGUUUCUCCUCUGGAUGUCUCAGGUGGACACUUGCCAUUGGAUUUAGGGCCCAUCAGGAUAAUCCAAGAUGAUCUUAUCUUGAGAUCCUUAACUUAAUUACAUCUACAAAGAUUCUUUUCAAAUAAGCUCGCAUUCAUGGGUUCUGAGGACUAGGACAUGGACAUAUCCUUUGGGGAGCCACGAUCAACCCAUUACACUCAUCUAUCAAAUGAGGAUGAUAUCGGUGCCUACCAUGUUAUGGAGUUUACAUGAGCUAAUGUGUCUCAUGCCCCGCACAGAGCAAACGUUUGUUCUUUUCAUAAUCUGUACUGAGCCACAAUUUUAUAAUUACUACGAUCAUCAUCACCAUCAUCAUAGCCAACUUUCAUUGAGAGGCUUCCCAAACUUAACACGUCUAAAAUUAACUCUUGACUCUUUCCCAGUCUUCAAUAGCUCAGUAAAUAGUACCUCUAUUAACCCCAAUGCACAGGCCAACAUCCUGCAAAUUAUCCACAUUUCUUCUUUUUCUCUCACACUUCAUUCCAUCCAUAAAUCUUGGCUGUUCUGUCUCCAAAAUAGAUCUCCAACCCAACCACAUCCUCGCAAGAGCCCCGUGUCGCACCCCCCCUCAGGUGCCCUUCAUGUUUUGAUGGGUGUGAGUGACGCUCCUGGAUUUAUAUAGGACACACGUGAGCAGCUACGUCAGUGAUGCUGCUUCUCACUGCCUCUACCACUGUCCCCCAUUCAAGACACCACUACCGGCCGGGCGCAGUGGCUCAUGCCUGUAAUCCCAGCACUUUAGGAGGCCAAGACGGGCAGAUCACCUGAGGUCAGGAGUUCGAGACCAGCCUGGCCAACAUGGCGAAACCCUGUAUCUAUGAAAAGUACAAAAAAAUUAGCCAGGCAUGGUGGUGCACACCUGUAAUCCCAGCUACUCGGGAGGCUGAGGCAGAAGAAUCGCUUGAGCCUAGGAGGCAGAGGUUGCAGUGAGCCGAGAUUGCACCACUGCACUCCAGCCUGGGCAAGAAAGCGAGACUCUGUCUCAAAAAAAAAAAAAAAAAAAUGCCACCACUACCUCCCACAUGGAUCACUGCAGUAGCUGUUGGCUGUCCUCUCACCUUCAUCUCUUGCCCCCCAACACCCCCUCAUGUCCUGCACAUACCCGUGACUGUCUACUCUCCUUGGAGCUACUUUUUAAAAACAUGGGUCAGAUUUUGUUUCUCCUCUGCCCCAGGCCUCCACUCAUUCCCCUAUCUCACUCAGAGCAAAAGCCAAGUCCUCCCAGUAGCCCCUGAGGCCCCACAUCCUCACCUGCCCCUCUGUCACUGUGCUGCAGCCCCUGGACCUGGGGCUCGCCCUGGGACACAGGCCACCUGUUUUGGCAUUUGCGCUGGCUGUGUUCUCAGCCUAGAACACUCUUUUCCCAGCUAUCAUUGUGGUCUUCUCCCUCACUGCACUAGCUGCUCACAUGUUUCGCAUGGAACUCCAAGGGUGCCAUUCACACCCACCAAAACGUGAAGGAUGCCUGGGGGGUGCGAGACGGGGGUCCUGGAAGGCUGUGAUUAGGCUGGAGAUCUAUUUUGCAGACAGAACGGCCAAGAUUUAUGGAUAAAAUGAAGUGUGAGAGAAAAAGAAGAAAGGUGGAUAAUUUGUAGGAUGUUGGCCUGUUCAUUGGGGUUAACAGAGGUACUAUUUACUAAGCUGUGGAAAACUGGGAAAGAGUCAAGAGUUAAUUUUAGACGUGUUAAGUUUGGGAAGUCUCUCAAUGAAAGUUGGCUAUGAUGAUGGUGAUGAUGACUGUGGUGAUUAUGAAGCUGUGGUCCUGCUUAAAAGAUACCCCCUGCAGGAGGCCCUUCCCUGACAAUCAUAGCUCAAACAGCACCCCAUCAAUCUCCAUCCCUUUAUUCUGGUUUUUCUUCAAAACAUUUAGUGCAAGGUCAGAUUGUCUGCUUUCCCCAUUACACCCAAGCUCCAUGAGGUGAAGGACUUUGUUUUGAUUCCUCCAGGAUCCUCAGUACCUGGCACAUGUGAGCCACAUCAUCAACAUUUCCUGGAUGAGGGCAUUAUUCUGGGCCAGGAACUGGCUUUGUAUGCAUGACCUCAUAUCUCCCAGCAGCCUAUGAGGUCUGGAUGUACCGACUGCUUUUGGAAUAAAAAGAUUCCCAGGAUGUGAGCAACACGGGACCGAUAUGAUGCUUCCUGGUGUGUUUAGUGGUUGGUGCCAUUCCAAUUUUCUGUGCUGAAAUCAUUCUGAAAACUCAAACAGUAGACUUCAGCACACAAGGAAAGCCAAAGCCAUUUGAGGGGGAAUAAAGCCAAAAGCCUUUCACCUUAUUCGUUCCAAGAAUCUCACCGCCCCCUCCUUAUCCCCCUCCAAAAAUAAGCCAUUGCACACAGACAGGCAGCAUGGCUAGCAAACGAAAAUCUACAACUCCAUGCAUGGUUCGGACAUCACAAGUAGUAGAACAAGAUGUGCCCGAGGAAGUAGACAGGGCCAAAGAGAAAGGAAUCGGCACACCACAGCCUGACGUGGCCAAGGACAGUUGGGCAGCAGAACUUGAAAACUCUUCCAAAGAAAACGAAGUGAUAGAGGUGAAAUCUAUGGGGGAAAGCCAGUCCAAAAAACUCCAAGGUGGUUAUGAGUGCAAAUACUGCCCCUACUCCACGCAAAACCUGAACGAGUUCACGGAGCAUGUCGACAUGCAGCAUCCCAACGUGAUUCUCAACCCCCUCUACGUGUGUGCAGAAUGUAACUUCACAACCAAAAAGUACGACUCCCUAUCCGACCACAACUCCAAGUUCCAUCCCGGGGAGGCCAACUUCAAGCUGAAGUUAAUUAAACGCAAUAAUCAAACUGUCUUGGAACAGUCCAUCGAAACCACCAACCAUGUCGUGUCCAUCACCACCAGUGGCCCUGGAACUGGUGACAGUGAUUCUGGGAUCUCGGUGAGUAAAACCCCCAUCAUGAAGCCUGGAAAACCAAAAGCGGAUGCCAAGAAGGUGCCCAAGAAGCCCGAGGAGAUCACCCCCGAGAACCACGUGGAAGGGACCGCCCGCCUGGUGACAGACACAGCUGAGAUCCUCUCGAGACUCGGCGGGGUGGAGCUCCUCCAAGACACAUUAGGACACGUCAUGCCUUCUGUACAGCUGCCACCAAAUAUCAACCUUGUGCCCAAGGUCCCUGUCCCACUAAAUACUACCAAAUACAACUCUGCCCUGGAUACAAAUGCCACGAUGAUCAACUCUUUCAACAAGUUUCCUUACCCGACCCAGGCUGAGUUGUCCUGGCUGACAGCUGCCUCCAAACACCCAGAGGAGCACAUCAGAAUCUGGUUUGCCACCCAGCGCUUAAAGCAUGGCAUCAGCUGGUCCCCAGAAGAGGUGGAGGAGGCCCGGAAGAAGAUGUUCAACGGCACCAUCCAGUCAGUACCCCCGACCAUCACUGUGCUGCCCGCCCAGUUGGCCCCCACAAAGGUGACGCAGCCCAUCCUCCAGACGGCUCUACCGUGCCAGAUCCUCGGCCAGACUAGCCUGGUGCUGACUCAGGUGACCAGCGGGUCAACAACCGUCUCUUGCUCCCCCAUCACACUUGCCGUGGCAGGAGUCACCAACCAUGGCCAGAAGAGACCCUUGGUGACUCCCCAAGCUGCCCCCGAACCCAAGCGUCCACACAUCGCUCAGGUGCCAGAGCCCCCACCCAAGGUGGCCAACCCCCCGCUCACACCAGCCAGUGACCGCAAGAAGACAAAGGAGCAGAUAGCACAUCUCAAGGCCAGCUUUCUCCAGAGCCAGUUCCCUGACGAUGCCGAGGUUUACCGGCUCAUCGAGGUGACUGGCCUUGCCAGGAGCGAGAUCAAGAAGUGGUUCAGUGACCACCGAUAUCGGUGUCAAAGGGGCAUCGUCCACAUCACCAGCGAAUCCCUUGCCAAAGACCAGUUGGCCAUCGCGGCCUCCCGACACGGUCGCACGUAUCAUGCGUACCCAGACUUUGCCCCCCAGAAGUUCAAAGAGAAAACACAGGGUCAGGUUAAAAUCUUGGAAGACAGCUUUUUGAAAAGUUCUUUUCCUACCCAAGCAGAACUGGAUCGGCUAAGGGUGGAGACCAAGCUGAGCAGGAGAGAGAUCGACUCCUGGUUCUCGGAGAGGCGGAAGCUUCGAGACAGCAUGGAACAAGCUGUCUUGGAUUCCAUGGGGUCUGGCAAAAAAGGCCAAGAUGUGGGAGCCCCCAAUGGUGCUCUGUCUCGACUCGACCAGCUCUCCGGUGCCCAGUUAACAAGUUCUCUGCCCAGCCCUUCGCCAGCAAUUGCAAAAAGUCAAGAACAGGUUCAUCUCCUGAGGAGCACGUUUGCAAGAACCCAGUGGCCUACUCCCCAGGAGUACGACCAGUUAGCGGCCAAGACUGGCCUGGUCCGAACUGAGAUUGUGCGUUGGUUCAAGGAGAACAGAUGCUUGCUGAAAACGGGAACCGUGAAGUGGAUGGAGCAGUACCAGCACCAGCCCAUGGCAGAUGAUCACGGCUACGAUGCCGUAGCAAGGAAAGCAACAAAACCCAUGGCCGAGAGCCCAAAGAACGGGGGUGAUGUGGUUCCACAAUAUUACAAGGACCCCAAAAAGCUCUGCGAAGAGGACUUGGAGAAGUUGGUGACCAGGGUAAAAGUAGGCAGCGAGCCAGCAAAAGACUGUUUGCCAGCAAAGCCCUCAGAGGCCACCUCAGACCGGUCAGAGGGCAGCAGCCGGGACGGCCAGGGUAGCGACGAGAACGAGGAGUCGAGCGUUGUGGAUUACGUGGAGGUGACGGUCGGGGAGGAGGAUGCGAUCUCAGAUAGAUCAGAUAGCUGGAGUCAGGCUGCGGCAGAAGGUGUGUCGGAACUGGCUGAAUCAGACUCCGACUGCGUCCCUGCAGAGGCUGGCCAGGCCUAGACAGGGAAGUCUGUUAGAACUGCUGUGCUGAUCAACGGGACGCUCCGUCUUUGAAGAAAGAAGAGAUGGUCUCUCCCCAGCCAUGGGCCACCCUUGCCAGUGACUCCAAGUGGAACUACUUAGCUCGCGUGUGCCUGGAGGGUGCGGGAAGUCCAGCGACUCUCAGACGCACCUCCCAGAGGACCGGUGGGAAUUGUUCAUAGUGCCAAAGUCCUACUACUGCGUUUUCAAUGGGUCCUUGUACAUAGUUUGCUCCUCUGCCCUAGCCCUCACCUCUUGCUAUACUGGAACCGAUUUGUACAAUGUGGGAAUUUUGUUACCUUUUUAAUCAAGGGCAACUUCCUUUUCCAGCACUACCAUUGUAAGGUUUUUUUCAGGAGGGAGGGCUAACCACCUUGCUUUUCUCUUUUCUCUUUUUCUUUUUUUUAUUUUUGUUUUAUUAAUUUGGGGAAAGGGGUGUUAGCAUUAGUGCCAUGAUAUCUACUGGAUUUUAAGUAGGGAGACUUUAUUUUUAAAGGUAGGUUGAAAUUUGGGAGAUUUCUCGGCAGGAAGGGCUGAAAUCCAGGCCCCUGUCUCAACUUGGAGAGAGGUGACAGACGGCAGAUCUUCCAAAUCAAAUUCCUUUCCAGUUCUUCCCCUGGCUGCCUUUUUGGGGGUCCCUGCCUUAGCCCCACACAAGGCUUUCUGAACUGCCAAGAGGGGAUCUGGCUUCUCAACUGCUCGGCCUCUUGGGCCAGGCUGUGCCCAGCCAGCCCUGGGAGAACUGGGUAGCAGGUGGCUGACUUCUUUAAGCACCUUUCUAAAUACCAGCAGAAGAGGCUCCCGCCUCUGUUAGCAUGAUCAGUACUAUUGUGACAUUAAAACAACAACAAUAAGAUCUUCCUAUCUGGAGGGUACAGAGGUGAAUGGCUUUGGUUUUCAUUUCUCUUCUUCACUGCCUUUUCUCGGUGUGGUAUUUGACAAGAUUUUAGCUCAAAGCCUCACCAUGAAUUGAUUUUUUUUGUUUGUGUGUGUGUUUGUUUUGGGACAAUUUUAGAUACCUGAGUGCACUUUUUCAGUUAGUCCUAACUUUUAAAAGAAGGAAAACCAAGAGACAUAUCUGGUGUACGUGUUGCAGUAUGAACUCUGGUUGCAAUCCCUCCCCGUCCCACACUGCCCCCCAUUUGAGUACACCGCACAAGUCAAACGCUAGGAAGUUUGAAUAAAACCAAUUUUUCUAACUUGUUGCUCAUUUGUUGUAACUCAAUAAAGCAAAGACUAAACAUUUUUAUAA